ACCUUGAUUGCUUCUUAGGCAGUGGUGAGGCGUCUUAGAGACGUGCAUCUCCAUGCGGUUGUACUGUCAGGCCAUGGGAAUUAGGAUCGGCUCUAUAGGACCAGUGUGAAGGGACAACGUGCGGCGGAGGGUCGAAGCCCACGGAUUUCCAUGAGCUCGGCCUGGCUUCCUUCUUGGAAUUGUUCGUUUCUCGGAGAUAAUUGUAUAAAAGAAGGAGAAAUAACCCCACAUCUCUUGACACUAGAGCUCCAGGUAUUUGCUGAUGGAUUGGAUGUAGAGUACGAGGAAGAAAUCAAGGAUGACUAGAAUAUUUCCUCUUCAUUUCAAAGGAGAGAAGUACCUCUAGGGGCAAAUCUGGACUUUUCUUUUGAACAUGUUUUUUGAGUUGCUUUUUAGACAUAAGAGUGGAGAUGGCAGGUUGCCAUGGAGUCAUCAGUGUGUAGAUUGUGUUGAAGGCCUGAGGCUGGAUAUGUUCACCAAGGGAGUGAAAGAAGAUAGAGAACUUUAUGUGCUGACUCUUGAGGCUUCCUGACCUGAAGAGUUCAGGGAUAGGAGGAGGAAGCACAAGGAAAAUUUUUACCCACCGGAAGUCUCUGGAAACCCUGAAAAUCAGCCAGUCAGAGGAAGUGAGGGUAACUUAGCAAGUUUGCUUCAGGUGUGGCCCCUGGACUCACUUUGUCAGCAUCCCCUGGAAACGUUUAAAACACAGACUCCUGGGCUCUACUGCAGAGAUACAGAAUUAGAAUCUUUGGAGCUGGACUCUAGCAGUCUGUUUUCAUCAUUGCUCAUGGUGAUUUUUAAACAUACUGAAGUUUGCAAAGCGCAGUCCUAGAGGAUCCUGAAGUUUGAGUUUAAGUGGCAUUGCGGUGGAGGCCUUGUUUCAGAUCUGGCCUCUACUCUUCCCUUUGUCCUUUGUGUAGGAGGGUAGCGUGUUGCCUGGUUGUCCACACCUGGGUCAAAGGGCAAUCCCCAGUUCAGGGCAGUGCAUGAAGGGAGGGAGAGAGAAAGAUGCUUGUCACUGUGGGCCAUGCAGAGGGCUGGUACAGAUGGUUAGAGGAAAGAAGGAGAUUUGAGUUCCUGAAGCAGUAAAAUCCAGUGAGUGUCCUAGAGUAGACAGCCCAAGUAUGUGUAUCUGUUUGUCUGAACUUGACCUUGAGACUUGAAUUUCAAGAGGAAAGAGGCCAGGCAAGGUGGGGAAGGGUGGAAACUCAUGUCCACUGUCUUUGCACUACCUCCCGAGUAGCUCUGAGCAGAUUGUAAGAGUUUUGUUCAAUCUGUGUGCAUCACCUCCUGCUGAUAGAAUUGCUUAGGACCCUUAAGUGCUUCCCGUGUGCCAGAGCCAUGAAAGGUAAAUAAAGAAAAAGAAGACUCAAUUAUUUUGAUGACUUAGAGAUCUGACCAUGGAGGCCGUGUGAAAGGUGGUAACCAGCAAUUUAUACCAUGUGUUGCUGGAUCCCAGAGUAAUUAAUUCAGUCUGGGGGGUGGGGCGGGGCAGAAGAGGCUUAAUUUUGAAAAGGAAUUCUUGCCCUGGGCUCCAUGAGCAUAACUCAGGAGUUCCAUGAAUUUGAAUGGGAAAAAAAUUAUACUAGUCUAAGUCACAAGUAGCAUUUCAUUGUGAACAUAGGUGCUAAGCCACAAUAUUAUUAGCAGUACUUGUGACUUUGUCAUCCAUAUACAUCAUAGAUAUUUUUAUGUCAUAUUCUGGUUUGUGCAAAUAUUUCAGAGUAUUGUUUAUGCUCAUUACUCUUUUGAAAUUGUAGUUAAAUUUAUUGUUUAUAUUGAAUGUAUUAAUAAAGUGGCACUAUACUUGCACAGUGAGCCAUGCAGAGUUUUAAUAGUUUUGAAGGUUGUAUUUCCAUAUAAUUCUUUGCAUUUCAUUUUAUGCAUUUAAAACUUUAUUCUCAGUAGGGAUCUUUAGGUAUCAUCAGAUUAGUGAAGGGGGGCCAUGGCACAAAAAAAGUUAAAAACGCUGACUAAAGAUGGCUCUAAUCUAUAUCCUGAUUUCUAUAAUCCCUAAGUAUGGGGAUUUAUUGUAUUUUAUUUUUUGCAAGUCAAACAGUAUUGCGUUAAUAAAGCUUUUCCUCUCCAGGUGUUUCUUCACAGGUCACAGGUCCCAUAUAUUUGUGGGGUCUCUCUGCCCUUCUGAGGGGCCCUGUGCCUUACUGAGAAUUUAGCUGCAGGACCCUCCUCACAGACUCUUCUGUGACUGUCCUUACCCAUCUGCAACACUCUUGGCUUUGUGGACUAUGAGCCCCUUCAGAGUAGGGGACUAAACCUAACAAGUACUCAGUAAAUGUCCUGUAAACUACUGAAUGAAUAGUAUCCAGGGGAUGUGAACCACAGCCUUGGGGCCCAGAAGAAAGGACUAAGUAAAGUUCCCUCCCGAACCUACAGGUCCCCUGACCAUGGGAAGCAGUCGCGCUCUGGACAGUAAAGGUGGAGACAGGAACUUGUCAGAGCUUGGAGAGUUUCCGGAAUGAAAAAGGCCUGGAUCUUCUGCGUCUCCAGCUUAGGAAAACCAGAGAAUAAAUACAGUUGCUGCUGCUCGCAGAGAACCUAGCAGAAGAGACCAUGGAGACUUUGACCUCAAGGCAUGAGAAAAGAGCUCUUCAUUCUCAAGCCUCAGCCAUUUCCCAAGAUAGGGAGGAGAAGAUCAUGUCUCAGGAGCCAUUGAGCUUCAAGGACGUGGCUGUGGUCUUCACUGAGGAGGAGCUAGAGCUGCUGGACUCUACCCAGAGGCAGCUGUACCAAGAUGUGAUGCAGGAGAAUUUCAGGAACCUACUCUCAGUGGGUGAGAGGAAUCCUCUGGGAGACAAGAAUGGAAAGGAUACGGAGUAUAUUCAAGAUGAAGAAUUAAGGUUCUUUUCACACAAAGAGCUCUCCUCAUGCAAAAUCUGGGAAGAGGUGGCAGGUGAAUUACCUGGGAGCCAAGACUGUAGAGUAAAUCUGCAAGGAAAAGACUUCCAGUUCUCAGAAGAUGCUGCUCCCCAUCAAGGGUGGGAAGGAGCAUCUACGCCGUGUUUUCCAAUUGAGAAUUUCCUGGACAGUCUACAAGGGGAUGGGCUUAUCGGUCUAGAAAAUCAACAGUUUCCAGCCUGGAGAGCUAUAAGACCAAUCCCCAUUCAAGGAUCUUGGGCAAAAGCGUUUGUGAACCAGUUAGGGGAUGUUCAAGAAAGAUGUAAAAAUCUCGACACAGAAGACACAGUAUAUAAAUGUAACUGGGAUGAUGACAGCUUUUGCUGGAUAUCUUGUCAUGUUGAUCACAGAUUCCCUGAAAUAGACAAGCCGUGUGGUUGCAAUAAAUGCAGAAAAGACUGCAUUAAAAACUCUGUACUUCAUCGCAUUAACCCUGGAGAGAAUGGCUUGAAAAGUAACGAAUACAGAAAUGGCUUCAGGGACGAUGCAGACCUUCCCCCGCAUCCAAGAGUACCUUUGAAAGAGAAACUCUGUCAAUAUGAUGAGUUUAGUGAGGGCUUGAGGCACAGUGCCCAUCUUAACAGACAUCAAAGAGUUCCCACAGGAGAGAAAUCUGUUAAGAGUCUUGAGCGUGGUCGGGGCGUCAGACAGAACACGCACAUACGUAACCACCCCAGAGCCCCUGUGGGAGACAUGCCCUAUAGAUGUGAUGUCUGUGGAAAGGGGUUCAGGUAUAAAUCGGUUCUUCUUAUUCAUCAAGGGGUGCACACAGGAAGGAGACCCUAUAAAUGUGAGGAGUGUGGGAAGGCAUUUGGUCGAAGUUCAAACCUGCUUGUCCAUCAGAGGGUCCACACUGGAGAGAAACCAUAUAAAUGCAGCGAGUGUGGGAAGGGCUUCAGUUACAGCUCAGUGCUUCAAGUCCAUCAGAGGCUGCACACAGGGGAGAAGCCCUACACCUGCAGCGAGUGUGGCAAAGGCUUCUGUGCCAAGUCUGCACUGCACAAACACCAGCACAUUCACCCUGGAGAAAAGCCCUACAGCUGUGGCGAGUGUGGAAAGGGAUUCAGCUGCAGCUCCCACCUCAGCAGUCAUCAGAAGACACACACCGGCGAGAGGCCCUACCAGUGUGACAAGUGUGGCAAAGGUUUCAGUCACAACUCGUACCUUCAAGCUCACCAGAGAGUUCACAUGGGGCAGCAUCUGUACAAAUGUAACGUGUGUGGUAAGAGUUUCAGUUACAGCUCAGGGCUUCUCAUGCAUCAGAGACUGCACACAGGAGAGAAACCCUACAAAUGCGAGUGCGGGAAGAGCUUUGGCCGGAGCUCCGACCUCCACAUCCAUCAGAGGGUCCACACAGGAGAGAAACCCUAUAAAUGCAGUGAGUGUGGGAAGGGCUUCCGGCGGAAUUCAGACCUUCACAGCCACCAGAGGGUCCACACGGGAGAGAGGCCCUACGUGUGUGACGUGUGUGGGAAGGGUUUCAUCUACAGCUCCGACCUCCUUAUCCAUCAGAGGGUCCACACUGGAGAGAAACCCUAUAAAUGUGCUGAGUGUGGCAAAGGCUUCAGUUACAGCUCAGGGCUUCUCAUUCACCAGAGAGUCCACACAGGCGAGAAACCUUACAGAUGCCAAGAGUGCGGAAAGGGCUUUAGGUGCACAUCAAGCCUUCACAAACAUCAGCGAGUCCACACGGGAAAAAAGCCCUAUACGUGUGAUCAGUGUGGCAAGGGAUUCAGUUAUGGCUCUAAUCUUCGCACCCACCAGAGGUUGCACACAGGAGAGAAACCCUACACUUGUUGUGAAUGUGGGAAGGGUUUCAGAUAUGGCUCAGGUCUCCUUAGUCAUAAGAGAGUGCACACUGGCGAGAAGCCAUACAGAUGCCACGUGUGUGGGAAGGGCUAUAGUCAGAGCUCACAUCUUCAAGGUCAUCAGAGGGUCCACACUGGUGAGAAACCCUAUAAAUGUGAGGAGUGUGGGAAGGGCUUUGGCCGCAACUCCUGUCUUCAUGUUCAUCAGAGAGUCCACACUGGAGAGAAGCCCUAUACGUGUGGUGUGUGUGGGAAAGGCUUCAGUUAUACCUCAGGUCUGCGGAACCACCAAAGAGUGCAUUUAGGCGAGAACCCUUAUAAGUAGAUGUACAUAGAGGAUUCCAUCUGGGACUCAGAGCUUUCUAUCCAUCUGAGAGCCAACACAGGAGAAAAACCAUAGGAAAGUGACAUGUAGGAGGGCUAUAGGAGAAACUGAUGAUUUUACAUUUUCUAGUCUGCAUAGGAAGGGAACACCUGGAUGUGUGAUAAAUAGGUUAGCACUUCAGUUACAAACUUCAGUCUUUAAGAGUCUGUUGUGCAGCGGAGUAGGCUUUAAAGAAACAGUGCAGCAGUGGUUUCAGUAAUAAUCCUCACUUCCAUCAGAAUCUGCCUGGGAGGGAGCUUUUACAAUGUACAAGUGGUGAGAAUGUUUCCAAGGUGCUAAUUAUGGACAUAGAUUCUUUGUGUGGGUUGAUAGCUACCAAUGGGACAGUGUAGAAACAAGUUUCCACCUUUCUAAAACCAGUUUGGUACAUAUCUUUUUAAAGAUCGCUUUAUAAAAACAAAAAGAUAACAUUAACAUUUAUUGAAACAAGUCACUCUGAGAAGACCAGGAACAAAGUUCUCUUGGCAGAUCUGGGUGAUGUGUGUGUCUCACAUUUUUAUCAUGUUUUUAUGACUGUUUUAUCUUGCAGGUAAGCUUUACAGCUUUCAGAGGAGUUGUAGUACACUACAGAAAUAUGUCUUCUUUCCAGGUUCAAAAAGCAAAAUCUGAUUGGCAUUGCAUUGAAUUAUUAAUUAAAUAAAUUUAUUAAUUGGCAUUGCAUUGAAUUUAUAGGUUAAUUUUGAAAGAAUGUGGCGUCUUUGAAAUGCUGAUUUUUUUUCACUUUAAAAAAAUGACUUUUUUUUUACCACUGAUAGUAUUUCAUAUGGUCCCUCAGUAAUAUUUCUUAGAGAUGGUUAAAAAUAGGUUCUGAGUCAUCUUAAGCAUAUUUCUAGGAAUUUGUUUUAUUGCUGUCAUGAAUAUAAUGGUUUUGCUCCAGUUCAUUUCAUAGUUUAACAUAUCAAAUAUUAGGUAUCUUAAAAAUCACAAAUGCUAUUUCACCCUGCAGGUUAGCAGUAUUAAAAUAGAAUCAUCAAAUCCCCCAUCAGUGGGGGCGGGGGGGGGGGUUGUAGAAACAGUCUGAUAUGGUUUGGCUCUUGUCCCCACCCAAAUCUCAUCUCAAUUUUAAUCCCCACGUGUCAGAGGAGGGCCUUGGUGGGAGAUGAUUGGAUCACGAGGGCAGAUUUCUCCCUUGCUGUUCUCAUGAUAGUGAGUUCUCAUGAGAGCUGAUGGUUUUAAGGUGUAGCCCUUCCUCGCUGUCUCUCUCCUGUCCCCUUGUGAAGAAGGUCCUUAUUUCUCUUUUGCGUUCUGCCAUGACUAAGUUUUCGGAGGCCUCCCCAGCCAUGUGGAACUGUGUGUGAGUUAAACCUCUUUCCUUUGCAAAUUACCUAGUCUCAGGUAGUUCUUUAUAGCAGUGCAAAAAUGGACGUAAUAAGUCUUAUGUACUUAUUGGUGAGAGAGAAAAUCCGUGCAUUGUUUUCAAAAGAAUUCAUUAACGUAUCAAUUCAAUUUCUAUAACCUUUGAAGUGGCAGUAAAUAUGUAGUAAUUGAUACUUGGGAGAUAGUUGCCCACUUGGGCAAAAACGCAUGCAGAAGGUGGAGUUUUUAAAUUUAAAACAUUUUUAAAAUAGCAAAUGUUAAUAUUCCAGUUUCCAUUGGUAGGAAAUUUUUUAGAUAAGUUCAGGCAUAUGUAUGCAAUGGAAAGCCACUAGAAAUCUUCAGGCACACAGAUAAUGACAAUGCAGGUUGCUCAUGAAGUAUUUAGUGAACCAGGAGAGUUUUAGAACAACAAUUAUAGCAUGACCCCAUUUUGUUAGUAUGUUUUUCUGUGUGUAUGUUUAGAGCAACAGAGAAAAAAAGAUGUGGGAGAGGACAUAUAACUACUUAUCUCUAGUGGUGGGAUUCUGAAUGUAUAAUACAUAUGUUGUACUUUUAUGUAUUUUACUUUGUAACAAAGUAUCUUUCAGUUUUAUAAUAACAGUAGAGCUAUUUUUUAUAAAUUAGCCUGAUGGAACAAUCCCUUAUGAUUAAAGAUUCAUGUUGUAACCUCUA